GCAGCCUGAGAUCCGUAAUAUGGCGGGGAGGAGGAGGAGAAGGCGGCGGCGGACCGAGCUGCGCUCUGUCAGUACCAUUUGAGCCAUUCGCUUCCUGACAAGGCCCGUGGCGAGGGGAGAGGAGCUGAAGGGGCCGUGGGGGAUCAGUUUCAUUUGAAACCUACGGGGAACCAAGCACUGUCGCUGCCCUCCAGGAAUUCAUACUCUACUGCUAAAAAUCGUCAUCAUCAUUAUCCUCUUAAUAAGAAAAGCAGUCCCCAUUAUUUGUUGCUUUCUGCGUGUUCUGCACUACGUUAAUUGCCCUACAUGCAUUAGCUCAUUGAAUUCUUACAACAUUCCUUUGAGACGGAUACCGUGAUCAUCCCUCUUUUACAGAGGACGAAACAGGUGUGGGGAUGGUAACUGGCUUGCCAAGAACUUGCAGCUAGUACGCAUCUGAAUAAGAAAUCUUCCCCUUUACCGCUUUUACAAGAAGUUUGCGUCUUUGGCGGAACUGAUGGGCAAAGAAACACUAGGUUCUGCAAAAAAAAAGCAGGAUCUGUUCUGUGUUACUUUUACCACUCUUUUCAGUGACAUGUCUGGCAGAGCACGGGUAAGGAGCAGAUAGGACCAUGAGUCUACGGGGUUUGCAAAGAGGCUCAUUUGCACAAGGGUCAGUGGUUCUCUGUGGUAUAAAUGGAGAAGACGGCAUGUCUGAACCUGCUGUAGCUGACAAAUUAUUACUGGAAGUGGACCAGUGAUGCCUGAUGGCAAGAUAUAGAGCAGUAGAUUUGUGGCUGGGGUAGCCUUGUAGUCAGGGCUCCCUUAAAAUAAAACCUUGCUGACAGUGGUAAUUGUAGUGUGAAAGGCAUAGUGUCCUCUUGCUUAAUCAUGGGAUACAGACUGCUCACUUCUUAAAUGGUUACCUUUGCAGUUUAAGAGGUACCAGUUUCUCUGGGACUAGAGCCAUGGUGAAAUUUCCAUUCUCUAAAUUCCACUCUUCCUUGCUAGCUUCGGUGUAUAGUCCGCCUUCUUUUUUUCUUCUGGUUUACAUUAUUGUUUGAGCUUAUUAUUAUUCUUAUUCAUUUAUUCAAUACUUUUAUCAAGUGCCUGCUGUGUGCUGAUACUGUUCUGUGUAAUGGGGAUUCAGUGAACAAGACUGAAAAGGUACCUGUACUUAUGGCGCUUACAUUUUGGUGGAGGAAGACAGACAAAAAUCAAGGAAAUAAACACGAUAAUUUCAGAUAGUGUGUGACUGUGGGAAGAUGGAGGAGUAUGAGAAGUUCUGUGAAAAAAGUCUUGCCAGAAUACAAGAAGCAUCACUAUCCACAGAGAGCUUUCUCCCUGCUCAGUCUGAAAGUAUCUCACUUAUUCGCUUUCAUGGAGUGGCUAUCCUUUCUCCACUGCUUAACAUUGAGAAAAGAAAGGAAAUGCAACAAGAAAAGCAGAAAGCACUUGAUGUAGAAGCAAGAAAGCAGGUUAACAGGAAGAAAGCUUUACUGACUCGUGUCCAGGAGAUUCUUGACAAUGUUCAGGUUAGAAAAGCACCUAAUGCCAGUGAUUUUGAUCAGUGGGAGAUGGAAACAGUUUACUCUAAUUCAGAAGUCAGAAACUUGAAUGUUCCUGCUACAUUUCCAAAUAGCUUUCCAAGCCAUACGGAACACUCUACUGCAGCAAAGCUUGAUAAGAUAGCUGGGAUUUUGCCAUUGGAUAAUGAGGACCAAUGUAAAACUGAUGGAAUAGACUUAGCUAGAGAUUCAGAAGGAUUUAAUUCUCCGAAGCAAUGUGAUAGUUCCAAUAUUAGUCAUGUAGAAAAUGAAGCUUUUCCAAAGACCUCUUCAGCAACCCCACAAGAAACUCUUAUUUCUGAUGGUCCCUUCUCAGUAAAUGAACAACAGGAUCUACCACUUUUGGCAGAAGUCAUCCCAGAUCCCUAUGUAAUGAGUCUUCAGAAUCUGAUGAAAAAGUCAAAGGAAUAUAUAGAAAGAGAACAAUCUAGACGCAGUCUGAGAGGUAGUAUCAACAGAAUUGUUAAUGAGAGUCAUUUAGACAAAGAACAUGAUGCUGUUGAAGUGGCUGACUGUGUAAAAGAGAAAGGCCAGUUGACAGGCAAACACUGUGUCUCAGUUAUUCCUGACAAACCAAGCCUUAAUAAAUCAAAUGUUCUUCUCCAAGGUGCUUCCACUCAAGCAAGCAGCAUGAGUAUGCCAGUUUUAGCUAGCUUUUCGAAAGUGGACAUACCUAUACGAACUGGCCAUCCCACUGUUCUAGAGUCUAAUUCUGAUUUUAAAGUUAUUCCCACUUUUGUUACCGAAAAUAAUGUUAUCAAAAGUCUUACAGGUUCAUAUGCCAAAUUACCUAGUCCAGAGCCAAGUAUGAGUCCUAAAAUGCACCGAAGACGUUCCAGGACAUCAUCAGCGUGUCAUAUACUUAUAAAUAACCCAAUAAAUGCCUGUGAAUUAAGCCCUAAAGGAAAAGAACAGGCAAUGGACUUAAUUAUUCAAGAUACUGAUGAAAACACAAAUGUGCCCGAAAUUAUGCCAAAGUUACCAACUGAUUUAGCGGGAGUUUGUUCAAGCAAGGUUUAUGUGGGCAAAAAUACAUCUGAAGUCAAAGAAGAUGUGGUUUUAGGUAAAUCAAAUCAGGUAUGUCAAUCUUCAGGAAAUCAUUUAGAAAAUAAAGUUACUCAUGGACUUGUUACUGUGGAAGGUCAGUUAACAUCCGAUGAGAGAGGCGCACACAUAAUGAACAGUACCUGUGCUGCGAUGCCAAAGCUGCAUGAACCAUAUGCCAGCAGUCAGUGUAUAGCAAGUCCAAACUUUGGAACUGUGAGUGGACUCAAGCCAGCCAGUAUGUUAGAGAAAAACUGCAGUUUGCAAACAGAACUGAAUAAGUCUUAUGAUGUAAAAAACCCUUCUCCUUUAUUGAUGCAAAACCAGAAUACGAGACAGCAGAUGGACACACCUAUGGUGUCCUGUGGAAAUGAACAAUUUUUGGAUAACAGUUUUGAGAAAGUUAAACGGAGACUUGAUUUAGAUAUUGAUGGUUUGCAAAAAGAAAACUGCCCUUAUGUCAUAACAAGUGGAAUAACUGAACAAGAAAGGCAACAUUUGCCAGAAAAAAGAUACCCUAAGGGAUCUGGCUUCGUUAACAAGAAUAAAAUGUUAGGAACUAGUUCCAAAGAAAGCGAGGAGUUACUAAAAAGCAAGAUGUUAGCUUUUGAAGAAAUGCGGAAGAGACUAGAAGAACAGCACGCCCAGCAAUUAUCACUACUCAUAGCUGAGCAGGAAAGGGAACAAGAAAGACUGCAAAAGGAAAUAGAAGAGCAGGAGAAAAUGUUAAAAGAGAAGAAGGCAAUGACAGCGGAAGCCUCUGAGUUGGACAUUAACAAUGCAGUGGAAUUAGAAUGGAGAAAAAUAAGUGACUCUAGUUUGCUGGAAACAAUGCUGUCUCAAGCGGACUCACUCCAUACUUCAAAUUCAAAUAGUUCUGGUUUCACAAAUUCUGCCAUGCAAUAUAGCUUUGUUUCUGCAAACGAAGCACCAUUCUACCUCUGGGGAUCAUCAACUAGUGGCUUGACCAAACUCUCAGUAACAAGGCCUUUUGGAAGAGCCAAAACUAGAUGGUCUCAAGUUUUUAGUCUGGAAAUACAAGCAAAAUUUAACAAAAUAACUGCAGUGGCAAAAGGAUUUCUUACUCGUAGACUUAUGCAGACAGAUAAGCUGAAGCAACUUCGACAAACUGUAAAAGAUACUAUGGAAUUCAUAAGAAGUUUUCAGUCAGAAGCACCAUUAAAGAGAGGCAUUGUUUCAGCUCAAGAUGCUUCACUUCAGGAAAGAGUGUUAGCUCAGUUGCGAGCUGCCUUGUACGGUAUUCAUGACAUAUUCUUUGUAAUGGAUGCAGCUGAAAGAAUGUCUAUUCUACAUCAUGAUCGAGAAGUUCGCAAAGAGAAAAUGCUCAGGCAAAUGGAUAAAAUGAAAAGUCCACGAGUGGCUCUUUCAGCUGCAACACAGAAGUCUCUUGAUAGGAAGAAAUACAUGAAAGCUGCUGAAAUGGGAAUGCCAAAUAAGAAAUUUCUGGUUAAACAAAAUCCUUCUGAAACAAGAGUCCUUCAGCCAAACCAAGGACAGAAUGCACCUGUUCAUAGGCUACUUAGUAGACAAGGAACCCCUAAGACAUCAGUGAAGGGGGUUGUGCAAAAUAGACAGAAGCCUUCACAGAGCAGAGUGCCUAACAGAGUGCCUGUUUCAGGAGUAUAUGCAGGAAAAAUCCAAAGAAAGCGGCCAAAUGUUGCGACAAUUUAAGAAGACAACAUUCAUUAGGAUAAAAUGGGGGGAAGGAUUAUUAUUCAUGUUAUUUUCCCUGCCCAAGACUUUAUUUAACCCUGGACUCCGUUUACACAGACAAAGUGACAUCAGAAGGCUGAGCACUUAUCUGGAUCAUUUGGUCAGUUUGGUAAUUCCUGCUCCACACCCCUAUUUUCCUCUUAAUAAUACGUUUGGGUGAAGACAAAUUAGUGUUUAGUAAUUGCAUCAUCUCUGUGCUUACCUAUACAAACAUAAGUUUAUUUUAUAUGCCCAGAUGUCUACAGAGACCCUUUUUGUAAAUGUCAAGGACAUUUGGAUUUACUUUUACAGAAUAUUGAAAAGAUAAGACAAAUUAUAAAUAAGUUCUAAAACAUAAAUUUAAUUCAUCUCUGCAUAGUGAUUUUUGAAUUUGAUUCAAAGGGAAAUUAUUGCAGAAGAAUGCCUUUCCCUCAUUUUAUAACUUUAAAAACUUGGAUUAACCACUCAAUGUCCACUUUCUUUGACUUACAGUAUAACCAUGUAGCCAAUUGUGGCCCACUAAAAUCUACAGAAGUUAAUGUGGGUCACCAUUUUGGUCAGAAGCAUACAUUCCUGUCAGACAACUAGUUGUCUGACAGAAAUGUUAGGCUUCAUGUAUGUUACCCCAGUACUGUUAGAAACAUUUGUACUAGGUUAUAAGAUCUUUCUGUGACAGGUAACAAAUUUGGGGAAGACAGCACAAUCUUCUUGAAUGUAGCUCUUGGGAAUGCAUUAUUACAUCCAUUUCUGUAACAUAAUAAUAUGUUGCAUGCAGUUAUAUUUUCUAUUUAGUCUGUAUAUUUUGUUCUUCAUAGUCUGUUUUUUCUAGCAUGCUUGAUUUAGGAGAGAAUAAAGGGCUAUAUAAUAAUAAAUCCAGAUUUCCGGAUAAGAAUAUUGCCUGGUUAAAAUUCUGCAUUGCUUAAAGACACCCAUGUUUAAGAUUUUUCAUCACUAACAUAUCCAUUAAAAGUAUCAACUGGCCAGGCAGGGUGGCUCACGCCUGUACUCCCAGCAUUUUGUGAGGCCAAGGUGGGUGGAUCACCUGAGGUCAGGAGUUUGAGACCAGCCUGACCAAACAUGGCGAAACCCCAUCUGUACUGAAAAUACAAAAAUUAGGCAUGGUGGUGCAUGCCUGUAGUUCCAGCUACUUGGGAGGCUGAGACAGGCGAAUUGCUUGAACCUGGGAGGCAGAGGUUGCAGUGAGCUGAGACUGUGCCAUUGCACUCCAGUCGGGUUAACAGAGCAAGACACUGUCUCAAAAAAAAAAAAAAAAAAAAGUAUCAACCAACAAAUGUUACCAAGAUAACGUGACUUCAUGAGGGAGAAUGUCACUAUUAAUUUAUCAUACCAUUUCCAAAAAGGGCUUUGUGCUUUUCACAUAAAAUUGAGACAGUGUAUAUUUAAUCUAAUUUAAAUUUUAAAGAGAUACUGGUAUUUUGAAAAUGCAACCUAUAUAUAUUCUUAAUAUCCUUUUAAGAAUAUGGAGAUGAAGAUUGUUUUCUCCAAUUUUCUGUGCCAUUUUAAAUUUAACUUUGACAUCCAGCUAUAGACAGAAAUAAUAAGCCACCCUGGGUGUAAACUUGAUUUUCUUUAUUGAGAUGUAUCAUGUAUUGAAUGAGUGAACCAGAAAAUUAGAAGAUGGUCAAAAAAAGUCCAAGUUACCAAUUUUUUAAAAUUUAUAGGCAAAGUAUCAAAUUGUCUUCUUAAUAUGAUAAACUGUGCUUUAUCAUUCUGAAAACUCAGGAUACAGCUUAUUCAUAGCAUUGUGGGUCUCUCCAGUAAGAAAGAUGCUAAAAGUUUUGUGCACUUUUUGUGUGUGUAAUGCAAAUUAGUUAAAACAAAUAGUUUUGGAGAAAGUUAAAACUAGCUUUAGAGUAAGGAUGAGAAACUUGAGUGUUUUUAAUUUAAAGAUAAAAGCCUGUGUUUUACACAUUCUUUUUUGGUGUUCAUAGCUUCUUCUCAUACAGGUGCCAGACACUGUUUGUGCUUUUGAUGGAUUUUUAUUUAUAUACUUUUUUUGCUUAUUUUUACUUUGAGUGGAAUGUUCAUUAAUGUAAAUUGUAUUUAUUUUUAUACUUUUAUUUUCACUAGUUUUGCUUCUAGGCAAAAAGCAAAAUAAACUUUUCAUCUUAAAGAAAA